AAGAUGAGGAGGUGGCAGAGAUUCAGGCCAGAGUUGUGGGCCGCCGUCGGCAGCAAGAACAGAGAGAGAGGUGGACAGAUCUGAGAGAUACUGAGGUCUUGCAGGAGGCGCUGCGACCAAUUCAAACAUGGCGCCGUCAGCCUCACAUUCCCCGUUUUCCGCUCAUGGCGGCGUAGGGGCGGAGGUCGCGCCUGAGUGCGUCCGCACGAGAGGGCGGAACCGUCUCCAUGGCAACCCGCGCGCAGCCGGGGCCACUCAGCCAGGCGGGAAGCGCUGGUGUUGCGGCGCUGGCGACAGUCGGGGUUGCGAGCGGCCCGGGGCCGGGGCGGCCAGGGCCGCUGCAGGACGAGACCCUGGGUGUGGCGUCCGUGCCCUCGCAGUGGAGGGCCGUCCAGGGCAUCCGCUGGGAGACGAAAAGUUGCCAGACGGCCAGCAUUGCCACUGCCAGUGCAUCCGCCCAGGCCAGGAAUCAUGUGGACGCCCAGGUGCAGACGGAGGCCCCCGUGCCUGUCAGCGUGCAGCCCCCGUCCCAGUAUGACAUACCCAGGCUCGCAGCCUUUCUUCGGAGAGUGGAGGCCAUGGUCAUCCGAGAGCUGAACAAGAAUUGGCAGAGCCACGCGUUUGAUGGCUUCGAGGUGAACUGGACCGAGCAGCAGCAGAUGGUGUCUUGUCUGUAUACCCUGGGCUACCCGCCAGCCCAAGCGCAGGGUCUGCAUGUGACCAGCAUCUCCUGGAACUCCACUGGCUCUGUGGUGGCCUGUGCCUACGGCCGGCUGGACCAUGGGGACUGGAGCACGCUUAAGUCCUUCGUGUGUGCCUGGAACCUGGACCGGCGAGACCUGCGUCCCCAGCAGCCGUCGGCCGUGGUGGAGGUCCCCAGCGCUGUCCUGUGUCUGGCCUUCCACCCCACGCAGCCCUCCCACGUCGCAGGAGGGCUGUACAGUGGUGAGGUGUUGGUGUGGGACCUGAGCCGUCUUGAGGACCCGCUGCUGUGGCGCACAGGCCUGACGGAUGACACCCACACAGACCCUGUGUCCCAGGUGGUGUGGCUGCCCGAGCCUGGGCACAGCCACCGCUUCCAGGUGCUGAGUGUGGCCACCGACGGGAAGGUGCUACUCUGGCAGGGCAUCGGGGUAGGCCAGCUGCAGCUCACAGAGGGCUUCGCCCUGGUCAUGCAGCAGCUGCCACGGAGCACCAAGCUCAAGAAGCAUCCCCGCGGGGAGACCGAGGUGGGCGCCACGGCAGUGGCCUUCUCCAGCUUUGACCCUAGGCUGUUCAUUCUGGGCACGGAAGGCGGCUUCCCGCUCAAGUGUUCCCUGGCAGCUGGAGAGGCAGCCCUCACGCGGAUGCCCAGCUCCGUGCCCCUGCGGGCCCCAGCACAGUUUACCUUCUCCCCCCACGGCGGUCCCAUCUACUCUGUGAGCUGUUCCCCCUUCCACAGGAAUCUCUUCCUGAGCGCUGGGACUGACGGGCAUGUCCACCUGUACUCCAUGCUGCAGGCCCCUCCCUUGACUUCGCUGCAGCUCUCCCUCAAGUAUCUGUUUGCUGUGCGCUGGUCCCCAGUGCGGCCCUUGGUUUUUGCAGCUGCCUCUGGGAAAGGUGACGUGCAGCUGUUUGAUCUCCAGAAAAGCUCCCAGAAACCCACAGUUUUGAUCAAGCAAACCCAGGAUGAAAGCCCUGUCUACUGUCUGGAGUUCAACAGCCAGCAGACUCAGCUCUUGGCUGCGGGCGAUGCCCAGGGCACAGUGAAGGUGUGGCAGCUGAGCACAGAGUUCACGGAACAAGGGCCCCGGGAAGCUGAGGACCUGGACUGCCUGGCAGCAGAGGUGGCGGCCUGAGGGGUCCCGGGAGGCGGGUGCAAGCCUUCGCUGUGCCGAGCCUUGUGUUUCUGACGCAAGCCAAAUGAAGAAAAGCAAAGCUUUGGGGGAA